CACCGCUAAGGCAGAGCAGCGUUCUCAGCACAGACCUUUGGGGCACUGCCUCGCUUUGGGACAACUCGGGACCGCAUAGACGGGAUCAUGGCACAAGUUGCAGUUUCCACCCUGCCCAUGGAAGAUGAGGAGUCCAUGGAAGAUGAGGAGUCUGUUGAAGAUUAUUCCGUGGAGAGCAGGAUGGUGGUGACAUUUCUCAUAUCAGCUCUCGAGUCCACGCAGUGUGUCCCCCAGAAAGUGUCAGAGCCUUUACGUGGACCUUCUCAUGAAAACGGAAACAGAAUAGUCAAUGGAAAAGGAGAAGGGCCUCCUGCAAAACAUCCUUCCUUGAAGCCUAGCACUGAAGUGGAAGAUCCUGCUGUGAAAGGAGCAGUACAAAGAAAGAAAGUACAGACAUUGAGAGCAGAACAAACCUUACCAGUGGCUUUAGAGGAAGAGCAAGAAAGGUGUGAAAGAAGUGAAAAGAAGCAAUCACAGGUCAAAGAAGGAAAUAAUACAAACAAAAGUGAAAAAAUACAACUAUCAGAAAAUGUAUGUCAUAGUACAUCUGCUGCUGCUGCUGACAGAUUAACCCAACAAAGAAAUAUUGGGAAAACCUAUCCUCAGCCUUUUACCAAGAAGCUGAAGGAAGAGCAUCAUAGAUGCAUCUUAAGAUAAGAAAAUAAAGAAAAAACAAAUGU